AUUCAUUGUCUUGACAAGAGCAUCUUCAGCGGGCGAGUCCCCGGCUCCUCCAGCUCCUUCCUCCUCUUCCUCCUCCUCCUCCACCUCCGGCUUUUGGGGGAUCACUGUCCUCUCUCGGCAGCAGAUACAGGCUGCUCCUCAAGACUGGGGCUCUUCACAUACGCUCCUCACCGCUCUUUGGGCAGGCCGACCUAGCAGCCUCUUCGGGAGUCCUGGGGUGGCCGGGGGUGCUGGAGCCCCCAAAUGAGCCGGCAGGUGGUCCGCUCCAGCAAGUUCCGCCACGUGUUUGGACAGCCGGCCAAGGCCGACCAGUGCUAUGAAGAUGUGCGCGUCUCACAGACCACCUGGGACAGUGGCUUCUGUGCUGUCAACCCUAAGUUUGUGGCCCUGAUCUGUGAGGCCAGCGGGGGAGGGGCCUUCCUGGUGCUGCCCCUGGGCAAGACUGGACGUGUGGACAAGAAUGCGCCCACGGUCUGUGGCCACACAGCCCCUGUGCUAGACAUCGCCUGGUGCCCGCACAAUGACAACGUCAUUGCCAGUGGCUCCGAGGACUGCACAGUCAUGGUGUGGGAGAUCCCAGAUGGGGGCCUGAUGCUGCCCCUGCGGGAGCCCGUCGUCACCCUGGAGGGCCACACCAAGCGUGUGGGCAUUGUGGCCUGGCACACCACAGCCCAGAACGUGCUGCUCAGUGCAGGUUGUGACAACGUGAUCAUGGUGUGGGACGUGGGCACUGGGGCGGCCAUGCUGACACUGGGCCCAGAGGUGCACCCAGACACGAUCUACAGUGUGGACUGGAGCCGAGAUGGAGGCCUCAUUUGUACCUCCUGCCGUGACAAGCGCGUGCGCAUCAUCGAGCCCCGCAAAGGCACUGUCGUAGCUGAGAAGGACCGUCCCCACGAGGGGACCCGGCCCGUGCGUGCAGUGUUCGUGUCGGAGGGGAAGAUCCUGACCACGGGCUUCAGCCGCAUGAGUGAGCGGCAGGUGGCGCUGUGGGACACAAAGCACCUGGAGGAGCCGCUGUCCCUGCAGGAGCUGGACACCAGCAGCGGUGUCCUGCUGCCCUUCUUUGACCCUGACACCAACAUCGUCUACCUCUGUGGCAAGGGUGACAGCUCAAUCCGGUACUUUGAGAUCACUUCCGAGGCCCCUUUCCUGCACUAUCUCUCCAUGUUCAGUUCCAAGGAGUCCCAGCGGGGCAUGGGCUACAUGCCCAAACGUGGCCUGGAGGUGAACAAGUGUGAGAUCGCCAGGUUCUACAAGCUGCACGAGCGGAGGUGUGAGCCCAUUGCCAUGACAGUGCCUCGAAAGUCGGACCUGUUCCAGGAGGACCUGUACCCACCCACCGCAGGGCCCGACCCUGCCCUCACGGCUGAGGAGUGGCUGGGGGGUCGGGAUGCUGGGCCCCUCCUCAUCUCCCUCAAGGAUGGCUACGUACCCCCAAAGAGCCGGGAGCUGAGGGUCAACCGGGGCCUGGACACCGGGCGCAGGAGGGCAGCACCAGAGGCCAGUGGCACUCCCAGCUCGGAUGCCGUGUCUCGGCUGGAGGAGGAGAUGCGGAAGCUCCAGGCCACGGUGCAGGAGCUCCAGAAGCGCUUGGACAGGCUGGAGGAGACAGUCCAGGCCAAGUAGAGCCCCGCAGGGCCUCCAGCAGGGUCAGCCAUUCACACCCAUCCACUCACCUCCCAUUCCCAGCCACAUGGCAGAGAAAAAAAUCAUAAUAAAAUGGCUUUAUUUUCUGGUA